ACCCUGCGUCACCUGCAGGCCCGGGCCGCGGGGUUGGUUUCCACCCUGGAGGUUGCUGACACCCUGUGCCCUCGGCUGACUUCCAGCCGGUGGCACAGACGCCUCCAGGGGGCAGCACUCAAGCGCAUCUUAGGAAUGACAGGUCCCUCAAACAGUGAGAUGUGGCUGUUUCCCAAGUCUUCCUCUCCAGUGUAAAGGGUCUGAAUUUAGACGCUUUGUGAGUCUUCCUUCUUUCGACAGCCUGGAGUCUCUCUUGAGUCUCAAGGCUGCCUGAGUUCCUCUCUAACAUCCUCUAGGCAGUAUCAGCUAAUGAGACAAUGAAUUCCAUGGAGGCAGCAGUGGGAACAGAAGUACCUCUCUUGGAUAAUUUACAACACUGAGUUGCGUCCCUCUCGGUUGCCAGGCUGGAGUUCAGUGGCAUGUUCAUAGCUCACUGAAGCCUCAAAUUCCUGGGUUCAAGUGACCCUCCUACCUCAGCCCCAUGAGGACCUGGGACUACAGUUCCCUCCCUUUGGAACGCAGCGUGGGCACCUGCAACGCAGAGACCACUGUAUCUCCGGUGCAGAAUGUAAUGAGUGCCUGAUACAUUUGCCGAAUAAACUAUUCCAAGGGUUGAACUUGCUGGAAGCAAGAGAAGCACUAUUCUGGAUGGAGUCUUGCUCUCGUUGCCCAGACUGGAGUGCACUGCUGCAAUCUCAGCUCACUGCAACCUCUACCUCCCAGGUUCAAGCGAUUCUCCUGCCUCAGCCUCUCGAGUGGCUGGGACUAUAGUAACAGCGGGAACAUGAAGCCGCCACUCUUGGUGUUUAUUGUGUGUCUGCUGUGGUUGAAAGACAGUCACUGCGCACCCACUUGGAAGGACAAAACUGCUAUCAGUGAAAACCUGAAGAGUUUUUCUGAGGUGGGGGAGAUAGAUGCAGAUGAAGAGGUGAAGAAGGCUUUGACUGGUAUUAAGCAAAUGAAAAUCAUGAUGGAAAGAAAAGAGAAGGAACACACCAAUCUAAUGAGCACCCUGAAGAAAUGCAGAGAAGAAAAGCAGGAGGCCCUGAAACUUCUGAAUGAAGUUCAAGAACAUCUGGAGGAAGAAGAAAGGCUAUGCCGGGAGUCUUUGGCAGAUUCCUGGGGUGAAUGCAGGUCUUGCCUGGAAAAUAACUGCAUGAGAAUUUAUACAACCUGCCAACCUAGCUGGUCCUCUGUGAAAAAUAAGAUUGAACGGUUUUUCAGGAAGAUAUAUCAAUUUCUAUUUCCUUUCCAUGAAGAUAAUGAAAAAGAUCUCCCCAUCAGUGAAAAGCUCAUUGAGGAAGAUGCACAAUUGACCCAAAUGGAGGAUGUGUUCAGCCAGUUGACUGUGGAUGUGAAUUCUCUCUUUAACAGGAGUUUUAACGUCUUCAGACAGAUGCAGCAAGAGUUUGACCAGACUUUUCAAUCACAUUUCAUAUCAGAUACAGACCUAACUGAGCCUUACUUUUUUCCAGCUUUCUCUAAAGAGCCGAUGACAAAAGCAGAUCUUGAGCAAUGUUGGGACAUUCCCAACUUCUUCCAGCUGUUUUGUAAUUUCAGUGUCUCUAUUUAUGAAAGUGUCAGUGAAACAAUUACUAAGAUGCUGAAGGCAAUAGAAGAUUUACCAAAACAAGACAAAGCUCCUGACCACGGAGGCCUGAUUUCAAAGAUGUUACCUGGGCAGGACAGAGGACUGUGUGGGGAACUUGACCAGAAUUUGUCAAGAUGUUUCAAAUUUCAUGAAAAAUGCCAAAAAUGUCAGGCUCACCUAUCUGAAGACUGUCCUGAUGUACCUGCUCUGCACACAGAAUUAGACGAGGCGAUCAGGUUGGUCAAUGUAUCCAAUCAGCAGUAUGGCCAGAUUCUCCAGAUGACCCGGAAGCACUUGGAGGACACCGCCUAUCUGGUGGAGAAGAUGAGAGGGCAAUUUGGCUGGGUGUCUGAACUGGCAAACCAGGCCCCAGAAACAGAGAUCAUCUUUAAUUCAAUACAGGUAGUUCCAAGGAUUCAUGAAGGAAAUAUUUCCAAACAAGAUGAAACAAUGAUGACAGACUUAAGCAUUCUGCCUUCCUCUAAUUUCACACUCAAGAUCCCUCUUGAAGAAAGUGCUGAGAGUUCUAACUUCAUUGGCUACGUAGUGGCAAAAGCUCUACAGCAUUUUAAGGAACAUUUUAAAACCUGGUAAGAAGAUCUAAUGCAUCCUAUAUCCAGUAAGUAGAAUUAUCUCUUCAUCUGGGACCUGGAAAUCCUGAAAUAAAAAAGGAUAAUGCAAUAAACACAGUUGCAGGAAAGUAUGUUAGCUAUAUACUAUGAAGUACUCUUAGUUUACUUAUGUUGAAUGGCUUAGCUAUUAAUACUCAAAUUGAGUUAAAAUGAAAAUUCCUCCUUAAAAAAUCAAACGUAAUAUGUAUUACAUUUCAUGGUACAUUAGUAGUUCUUUGUAUAUUGAAUAAAUACUAAAUCACC